GCACUCACCUGCUCUUCCUGGGCUGGCUGUCUCCUGCUCAUCCAGCCAUGCGGUGGCUGUGGCCCCUGGCUGUCUCUCUUGCUGUGAUUUUGGCUGUGGGGCUAAGCAGGGUCUCUGGGGGUGCCCCCCUGCACCUGGGCAGGCACAGAGCCGAGACCCAGGAGCAGCAGAGCCGAUCCAAGAGGGGCACCGAGGAUGAGGAGGCCAAGGGCGUGCAGCAGUAUGUGCCUGAGGAGUGGGCGGAGUACCCCCGGCCCAUUCACCCUGCUGGCCUGCAGCCAACCAAGCCCUUGGUGGCCACCAGCCCUAACCCCGGCAAGGAUGGGGGCACCCCAGACAGUGGGCAGGAACUGAGGGGCAAUCUGACAGGAGCACCAGGGCAGAGGCUACAGAUCCAGAACCCCCUGUAUCCGGUGACCGAGAGCUCCUACAGUGCCUAUGCCAUCAUGCUUCUGGCGCUGGUGGUGUUUGCGGUGGGCAUUGUGGGCAACCUGUCGGUCAUGUGCAUCGUGUGGCACAGCUACUACCUGAAGAGUGCCUGGAACUCCAUCCUUGCCAGCCUGGCCCUCUGGGAUUUUCUGGUCCUCUUUUUCUGCCUCCCUAUUGUCAUCUUCAACGAGAUCACCAAGCAGAGGCUACUGGGUGACGUUUCUUGUCGUGCCGUGCCCUUCAUGGAGGUCUCCUCUCUGGGAGUCACGACUUUCAGCCUCUGUGCCCUGGGCAUUGACCGCUUCCACGUGGCCACCAGCACCCUGCCCAAGGUGAGGCCCAUCGAGCGGUGCCAAUCCAUCCUGGCCAAGUUGGCUGUCAUCUGGGUGGGCUCCAUGACGCUGGCUGUGCCUGAGCUCCUGCUGUGGCAGCUGGCACAGGAGCCUGCCCCCACCAUGGGCACCCUGGACUCAUGCAUCAUGAAACCCUCAGCCAGCCUGCCCGAGUCCCUGUAUUCACUGGUGAUGACCUACCAGAACGCCCGCAUGUGGUGGUACUUUGGCUGCUACUUCUGCCUGCCCAUCCUCUUCACAGUCACCUGCCAGCUGGUGACAUGGCGGGUGCGAGGCCCUCCAGGGAGGAAGUCAGAGUGCAGGGCCAGCAAGCACGAGCAGUGUGAGAGCCAGCUCAACAGCACCGUGGUGGGCCUGACCGUGGUCUACGCCUUCUGCACCCUCCCAGAGAACGUCUGCAACAUCGUGGUGGCCUACCUCUCCACCGAGCUGACCCGCCAGACCCUGGACCUCCUGGGCCUCAUCAACCAGUUCUCCACCUUCUUCAAGGGCGCCAUCACCCCAGUGCUGCUCCUUUGCAUCUGCAGGCCGCUGGGCCAGGCCUUCCUGGACUGCUGCUGCUGCUGCUGCUGUGAGGAGUGCGGCGGGGCUUCGGAGGCCUCUGCUGCCAAUGGGUCGGACAACAAGCUCAAGACCGAGGUGUCCUCUUCCAUCUACUUCCACAAGCCCAGGGAGUCACCCCCACUCCUGCCCCUGGGCACACCUUGCUGAGGCCCCAGUAGGGGUGGGGAGGGAGGGAGAGGCCGCCACCCCCGCCGGUGUCUGCUGUUCUUUCCCCAUAGGUCUUGCUUUGUUGCCUGUCUUGCUGUCUAGGGAUGGACUUGGUUCCUCUUGUCAAGGUUUGGGAAUGUCAAAGCCCCCUCCCCACACAGGGCCUUUCCUGUCCCUUGUGGGGCCUUCCAACCCUGUCCUUUCCACUGGUGGGCGGUGAUGCUUCUAGGUCCUUAGAACUGCCCAGAAACUCUGAGUCCCAGCAGCUGGGAGCCAGAACUUUGCCUGCCCUCCCUUGGUUCCAGUCUCUCUUCUCUCUCUCUGCCUUGGAACCUGACCAUACUUUAGUUGUGCCCUUCCCAGGCAUCAUCCUCCUACCACCAACCUGGGGCCCCAUCUUGGAAUGGGGGCUCCUUGGGGCCAGCCCAGUGUGGCUCACCACACUCUUCUUUUUUUUUUUUUUUUUUUUUGAGAUGGAGUCUUGCUCUGUUGCCCAGGCUGGAGUACAUUUGCCUGAUGUCAGCUCCCUGCAACCUCCGCCUCCUGGGUUCAAGCGAUUCUCCUGCCUCAGCCUCCUGAGUAGCUGGGAUUACAGGUGUGCACCAACACACCCGGCUAAUUUUUGUAUUUGUAGAAGAGGCGGGGUUUCACCAUGUUGGCCAGGCUGGUGUUGAACUCCUGACCUCAAGUGAUCUGCCUGCCUUGGCCUCCCAAAGUGCUGGGAUUACAGGUGUGAGCUGCCACGCCCAGCCCCAGUACACUCUUCUCUGGACCAGAUCUGUCCCAGUCCUGGAUGCCUCCUCCUACUGGUGCCUUCUUUUCUUCCAGAGGAUUUCUCUCUCCUUCCUCCUCCUUUCUUUGGGAUCCCUGGGUUGCCCUGUCCCAACCUCCUUGUUAGGUGCUUUCCCAUAGGAGGCCCUUCUUGAGAAACAAUAAACUAGGUAGAACUACCCCUAUGCCCAUCCACUUUCUUGUGCCACAUUCUGGCAGGGCCCAGAUGCAGCUGGGCCUUCCUGGCCUGGCAGUGCCUAGGAGAAUUUCUCCUGACCUGGCCUGGCCUGUGGCUGAUGUUCAGAACAGCCUUGUGGCCGAUGUUCAGAACAGCCUUGUGGCCCUGGCGACUCCAAGGGUUUUAUGGCUUUUGAGGGACAGAGAGGAUGGAGGGCUUGGGGAGCCGGAGGACCUAAGUCCUCAUCCUGGCCUAAACCCCAUGCUCCUUGGGAAGUCAAAAGCCUGGAAAAUAUCUCCUCUGGAGCCUUCAUCUCUGCUAUGCCCUCUCUCCACAAAGCCCCCCUUGGAGGGAGUCCAGUGGUCUUUCCUCUGUGAGCCCCAGGGCUUCCCAGCCUUUGUCACUCUGAGAGCUGCUCUUGUUCAGUUUCUUAGAAUGGACUGUUUUGCCUGUAGACGGCCCAGCUGCCUGCCCUGGCCUGCCCCCACCCAGCCCCCACUGCACCACCCUUCCCGCCAGAGCUCCCACUGCCCCCGGCAGACCCUUCAUGCAGCUUCUCCUGUGGGGUCUUGCCCUUGAAGUGCCACUUCCCCCAGCCCCACCUCUGGUCCCUUCCAGAGGGCACCCUUAGCCUUGUAGGUCCCUGGGAAGCUGGCACAGCAUCAACCAGAAGUGAUGCCUCAGCCAGGCCACCAGUCGCUCCCCGCCUGGGAGCUCAGCUUUCCUCAGAACCACCCCCCCUGUCUGAAGCUCUGUCCUGGGUCCCACCAGACUUCUGCCCACCAGGCCUACCUACAGCAUCCACAUGGGGCCUCAGGAAGGGCCCCGGGGGCCCAGGGAUGGGCAGGGGCAGGGUUUCCAAGCGCCUGGGGCUCCAUUCUCCUCUGUCCACCCACCCACACCCCUUGGCCUCAGCCUGCCCUGUACCCAAGCUUCCCUCCCCCUCUCCUGGGGAUCUUAACGGCCUUGUUCUCUCUCCCUGGCACCCACCCCCAGGGCGGGUGAUGCCGCCAAGAGAGAGGGAGGCCGUUGCUAGGUGAUGGCGCCGCCAUGCACACACCCUUUGUGCUGGGGAGUGACACCCACCCGUUUCUCAGCAGACCUGUUGCCACGGUGACUGAAGCCCCCAGCUCUGUCUGUAGAAACUUCAGAUGGGUGGGGGAGCAGGUUGGAGAGGGGACCAAAGGCAGGCCUGUCGUGCUGAAGCUCUUGGGGACCGUUUCCUCGGCAUUUCCCCAACUCCUUCUCCACCCCCCUGCCAGGCCCGGAAGUACCACCAGCUUCCUAAGGGAUGCAGGAAGGGGCCGGGUGAACUGAGGUGAAGUCCAGGGCAGGGGAGUCAGACCCCUCAACAUCCUGUUUAGGGGUCCUCCUCCACAAAGGGUGCCCUCCACCUCUCCCUCCUGCUGGUUGGCCGGCUCAGAGAUGAAGGGGGAGAGAUGGUGGCUCCAAGGCUCUGCCACCGCCACCUCCCAAGCCUGCCAACGUGAAUGGCUUGCAGAAUCAGUCAGCAGGCCAGCGGCCUUGGGAAAGAGCCACUGUCCUCGCAGCCUGGGCCAGCUGGGGGAACAAUGUAGGGUUUGUUGCUUAGGGGUCCCAGGCUUGCGGGGGGGUUGGCACAUGGUGGGCAGUGGACUUGAGCUGGGAUGGUCUGAGGGGGCACUGACACGCUCACCCGAGGGCAGACUUCAGACCAGCCCUCAGAUCCUGAUGCCAGGUUACAGGGCUGAGGGGAGCCUGAAAUCCACUGGGUCUCCCUGCUCCACUUGGGAGUCACCUUCUCAUCACCUAUCCUGGAACUGAAUGCAAUUACUUAAACUCAGUCUCAGCUUCCUCAUCUGUAAAAUGGGAAUAAUCUGUCCUUCACAGAGGAUUAUGGUCAUUUAAUGAGACAAGAUACAUAAAGCACUUUGCAUGGUGCCCCGAACCUUUUAUUCCUUCCUCUCCUUUGGGAAUUCAAUUCUCUAGUGUUAGGAGCAGGCUUGGCCCAGGGAUUCUUAAAUGCAUCCAGGUUUUGGCAUCAAAGGGCCCCAAACAUGACAAUUUACCUAUACUCAUGGUCUGUUCCCAUUCAACUUUAAUAGGUUAUGUGUGUUUUUUUUUUCUUAAGAGCUGGGUGGGGGGGUCUCACUAUGUUGCCCAGGCUGGCUUUGAACUCCUGGGCUCAAGCAGUCCUCCUGUCUCAGCCUCCUGAGUAGCUGGGACUACAAGUGUGUACCACCAUGCCUGGCUGAACACUUUUUUUUUUUUGAGACAAGAUCCCACUCAGUCACUCAAGCUGAGUGCUGUGGUGUGAUCACAGCUCAUUGCAGCCUCCACUUCCUGGGCUCAAGCGAUUCUCCUGCCUCAGCUUCCUGAGUAGCUGGGACUACAGGUGCGCACUACCACGCCUGUCUAAUUUUUGAUUAUUUGUAGAGAUAGGGUCUCACUAUUUUGCCCAGGCUGGUCUCAAACUCCCAGACUCAAGUCAUUCUCCUACCUCGGGCUCCCAAAGUACUGGGAUUACAGGCAUGAGCACCUGGCCCCUGAACAAAUUCUUUAAGUCAUAUUAGCACCUGCUGCACGCCGGCACUGUGGAAGGAGGAUGCUUGCUUGCUUCCUGGUAACCAGCUCUCUUAUCUCAAACCUCAAUCCUCAGUGAGGAUCACAGGAUCUGAGAAAGGCACCUUGGCCUGGAAACAGCCCCAGAUGAGUGAGAUUGCUGGUCCUCUCCCGGGAUCCCAGGCCCAGGAAAACCUAGCCAUGCUUGCAGUCAGGAGAGGGCAGGGGAUAGAGCCCUGGCUCCCAUUCAACCUCCUUAGCCAGGAGGACAUGUCCCAUUUUGCUUAGGAGUUGGGAGGUACCCUAGAAUCACUUAGCUUCAGAUGCCAAAUUCCAUCCACAUUCUUUCCUCCAACUCUCUGGCAGUGGGGAACUGCCUCUCCAGGCAGGGAACUGCUCUGACAGGUCUGAUGACUGCCUCCAGGAGGAAGCCCUGGGCACCAAUGAAGGUGAGGGGCUGGAGGGCCCAGGACGGGGAGUCAAGGUCCCCACUCCCAGGACUAAGGGACAGUUUGGCUCCUUUUUCCUGCAGUGGGAGGGGUGAGAAGGGCUGGGGUGUUCUGCAAGGGCCUGCUCCAUUUUCCAGGGUGAAGGAGAGGCCGAGGGAGGUGGAGCGGGAGGAGGUGGGGCUUACUGUGAAACUGGGUCAAGAUGGCCUCGGAUUUGAGCAGGCAGGGUCACCAGGCUCUGAGGCAGCAGCUGUGAGCAGUGCCGAGGGAGGACCAGCUCUGACGGUGAGGUCGGGUGGGGGACUAGAAUCCAGCAGAGGAGCGAGGGCAGGGCUCCUACCAGGAAACCCAUAGCAUUGACACUAACUGAGAGGCAGCAAAGGCGGUGACACUCCCCCAGGCUCUGUGGGCCCAGCCCUACCCCUGAAGCACAGUUAACUGGUUCUGGGGUAGGAACUGGGGGCCGGAGGGACAGGGUUCUGGUUCUGGCUCAACCUUGGCUGCUGGUGAGAUCCAGGGCCUGGGAAAGAGGGGCUGAGGCCUGAACUGGGCCUAAGGAGAGUGCAGCUCAGUUCGCACACAACAGCACCCAGCCCUGUCCCCUUGCUGCCUCUACCCAGCCCUGGGCAGUUCCCUCAACAGAGCUCUGCAGCCCCAAGUGGCAGCUGCUGGCUCAAAGCUGGGACUACAUGAAAGUCUGAAAAGAGAAUGAGAAGGAGGUGGCGCAAGAGCCUGGACGCACGUGUGGGAGGCCGUUUUGUGCAGCGCCAUUGUGCUCCCCGGGCGGGCAUGUGCUCGCGCUCCGUGGCUCUGUUGGUGCCCAGCGUGCGGGGGUGUGCUGGUGGCCCUGUGGGCCUGUAGGGCAACCCAUGCCAACUGCGGAAAAGUAACCAGCACCAUACACCCCCCCCAACACAAAACUGGUCAUUUAUUUUUUUUGUUGUCAUUGUUAUUAGGAAGCAAAAAAAUGUACAGUUACAAGAAUCAUUUUCCAAACAGAGGUUAAAUAUGAGCUGAAAAGUGUAAAAAAGGAAGAGGAACAUCACUUUACAAAUCAUUAAAUUAAACAAAUAAACAAACAGAACCCAAAGAACCAA